UCUACCCUUUUUGAGAAUAAAAUCAUCUACAAAGUUUUCCGGCCGGGCGCAGUGGCUCAUGCCUGUAAUCCCAGCACUUUGAGAGGCUGAGGUGGGCGGAUCACGACAUCAGGAGAUCGAGACCAUCCUGGCUAACAUGGUGAAACCCUAUUUCUACUAAAAAUACAAAAAUUAGCCAGGCGUGUGGUGUGUGCCUGUAAUCCCAGCUACUUGGGAGUGUGAGGUAGGAGAAUUGCUUGAACUGGGGAGGCAGAAGUUACAGUGAGCUGAGAUCGCACCAUUGCACUCCAGCCUGGCAACAGAGUGAGACUUAAUCUCCAAUAAAAUAAAAAGUUUUCCAUACCAAAUCCUUUUCCACUUGAAAAGGCACCUUCUUAACCAGUUUCCAUUUUAAAUGCUUAAGGUUUUAUCUGUUUCAUGUUGCUUUUUAAAAAAAUAAUCUUCAUAAUGACCCAUAUUACAAGAUGCUGAUUAAAAUUGUUUAGGUUUACUGACUUUCUUUGUAGCAUAUUGUUAUGGAAAUAUUUUCACCCCCUCACUUCCUACUACAGAAACAAAAGGAAAUAUAGCAAGUCUAAUUUUGACAUUUAGUAAAAAUGACAGAAAAUGACUCAUCUCGUGGUGGUUCAGUUUUCUUGAUGUCCCGAGGUUCUGCUAAGUACCAGGCCUUCCACCAGGUGCUCCCGUGAAAAUGAAGGGCUUGUGAAAUGCAUCUCCACCAAAACGGCUACCAAGUUCUUUACACUUCAAAAAUUAUGCUUCACACUUACGUGAAAUAGAAUAUUAGGUUCUGGACAAAGAUGGUCCAUUCAGGUUCAUCCAAGGAAAUCAUAAAACAGGCCCAUGGAGUGUGGGCGGCGACCCAACACCAUUGGCGUCCUUGGACAGUUCUCAAUGUGGUUGUGACGGGCAGACAUCCAGUUGCUUCCCAGCCCUGGGGUGGCACGUGUCUGCAGAGUCGUACAAGUUUCAUGUAGAAGAUGUACUUAAUGUGGUACAGCAGAGUUUAAGGAUUUAGUAGGGGACGUGGGCUUCCUGGAUUUUACUGACACCUAAGUCCUCACUCAGCCUUUUAAGCAGCUGUGGCAAAUCAUUGACCCUUUCAUUCAGUACUUCCCCUGUUUGUAAAAUUGGACUAUUAAGAUCUCCCCCUUAACUUAGCCAUGUGAUUAUGUUGUGACGUUUAACUGAAUGAUGAUUUUUACAGUGUUUGGGGGCUCCUGUACUGGAGGAACAGUGUAAAUAUAAUACACUGUUAGCAUGAUAUUGACCGACAGUGAAGCCGACAGUUGUGGUGGCCAAUGUUGUUAUUUUUUGCCUCACUGACCAAAUCUUUCUCUCUUCUCCUCUUUGUCUUCCUCUUCCUCUCCUUCCCUCUUCUCUCCCUUUUAUUCUUCCUUCCUUUAAUACUGUCCUGCCCUUACAAAAACGAUGAAGAGAAACAGCCUUUAAUGUUGGACCUCUCAGCUCUGCCACCCCCACCAGAGCCAGCCUGUCCUCGUCUCCCCUGCCCCUUUCUCUUCACCGUGGCCUCAGUCAUCUUUGAAUGUGAAUCAAAUCCAAUCACAUCCUUCACCCUUGAAAAAAUAAAUUUUAUUUUGACGUACCCUAUACACACAUGUGAGGAGUUGAAGGAGUGAGCCAAUGGGAAAUUACAGAUGCCCACCCUCCGGUCUAAGCCUCGGAGCUGCCAGGCCAGUGAAGCCCCCGCUGCAGCCCCAGGUCUGCCUCCCUGCGGGACCAGGGCACCCGGGGCCUCACAGCUGUGCGGGUCCUGCCUGUGCCUCUCUUUGUGGCGUUCCAGCCUGUGUAUGCUUCCCUAAGUGGGAUGCUGAGUCCUGUUGACAGGAUGGGAAGUGGGCACUGUCCUCAUUGUUCAGAGAGGGCCCUUUCCCUACUCUGAAGAGGGAAGAAAGCUGGAUGUGGUCUGGGCACCACACUGGCUUUGCUUUUCCUCAGAGUGGAUGAGGAUUCAGUAGGUGAAGUCGUGAGCUAAUUUUUUUUUUUUUUGGAGAAACGGUGUCACUCUGUAACCCAGGCUGGAGUGCAGUGGGGUGAUCAUAGCUCGCUGUAGUGUCAAACUCCCAGGCUCAAGCCAUCCUCCUGUCUCAGCCUCCCAAGUAGCUAGAACCACAGGCAUGCACCAGCACACCUAGCUAAUGUAUUAGUUUGUUCUCAUGCUGUUAGGGAAGACAUACCUGAGACUGGGUGAUUUAUAAAGGAAAGAGGUUUAAUUGACUCACAGUUCAGCAAAGCUGGGGAGGCCUCAGGAAACUUAAAAUCAUGGCAAAAGGGGAAGCAAAGAUGUCCUUUUUCACAUGGCAGCAGGAAGGAGAAUAAGAGCUGGAUGAAGGGGGAAGGCCCUUAUCAUCAGAUCUCAUGAGAGCUUACUCACUAUCAGGAGAAUAGCAUGGGAGAAACCGCCUGCAUGAUUCAAUUACGUCCCCACAACAUGUGGGGAUUAUGGGAGCUAUAAUUCAAAAUGAGAUUUAGGUGGGGACACAGCCAAACCAUAUCAGCUAAUUUUUAGAUUUUUUGUUUCUGUACAGAUGGGGUCUCACUGUGUUGCCCAGGCUGGUCUCAAAUCCUGGGCUCAAGUGAUCCUCCUGCCUUGGCUUCCUAAAGUGCAGGGAUAACAGGUGUGAGCGACUGCACCUGGUCUGUGAGCUAAUCUUAAGAAGACGAGGGGUUACCACACUUGCUUCUACUGAAGUUGCAGCAUGAACUCUCAGUACUGGAGGUCACAUCCCUUAGAAAUGUGGGCAGGGGCUGCAUAGUAUUCCAUGGUGUAUAUGUGCCACAUUUUCUUAAUCCAGUCUAUCACUGAUGAACAUUUGGGUUGGUUCCAAGUCUUUGGUAUUGUGAAUAGUGCUGCAAUAAACAUCCGUGUGCAUGUGUCUUCAUAGCAGCAUGAUUUAUAAUCCUUUGGGUAUAUAUCCAGUAAUGGGAUGGCUGGGUCGAAUGGUAUUUCUAGUUUUAGAUCCUUGAGGACUCGCCACACUGUCUUUCACAAUGGUUGAACUAGUUUACAGUCCCACCAACAGUGUAAAAGUGUUCCUAUCUCUCCACAUCCUCUCCAGCACAUUGGGACAUGGAUGAAGCUGGAAACCAUCAUUCUGAGCAGAGUAUUGCAAGGACAGAAAAUCAAACACCGCAUGUUCUCACUCAUAGGUGGGAAUUGAACAGUGAGAACACUUGGACACAGGGUUGGGAACACCACACACUGGGGUCUGUCGUGGGGUGUGGGGAGGGAUAGCAUUAGGAGAUACACCUAAUGUAAUUGGUGAGUUAAUGGGUGCGGUACACCAACAUGGCACAUGUAUACAUAUGUAACAAACCUGCACGUUGUGCACAUGUACCCUAGAACUUAAAGUAUAAUUUAAAAAAAUACAUUAAAAAAAUGUGGGCGGGGGUUGGUUGGUUCUUGUUUUCUGAUUUUACAACUUAGCUCUCAGGAGCAGGCUGAAGUUCACUGUUUCUUUGCAGUGGAAUGAAUGUUCUCAUCUUGUCUAGACAGCUGGACCAGGAGUAGGACCCAACUUAGGAAUCUUUUUAGUGUAGUCAAAAUAAGCUGAAUAUUGUUAACAAUCUUGGUCUGGCUGACUUUGGCAUUGUGUCCGUAGGUUGCAAAGAUGAUAAAAUGCUGUCUACAUUUCCUUCUCACUAAAAGUGGCUAAAAAUGUCUGUCUUAUCCAUAUACUUUAUUGAUAGUUUGUGUGGGUGUAGAAUUUUAGGUGAGCUAUCAUUUGUCUCAAGAAUCAGAGGUUUUGGCUGGGGCGUUGGUGGCUCACGCCUGUAAGCGCAGCACUUUGGGAGGCCGAGACGGGCAGAUCAUUUGAGGUCAGGAGUUCUAGACCAGCCUGGCCAAUAUGAUAAAACCCUGUCUCUACUAAAAAUACAAAAAAAUUAGCCGGGCAUGGUGGCAUGCAUCUGUAAUCCCAGCUACUCAGGAGGCUGAGGCAGGAGGAUUCCUUGAACCCGGGAGGCAGAGGUUGCAGUGAGCUGAGAUUGCACCACUGCACUCCAGUCUGGGCGGCAGAGCAAGACUCUGUCUCAAAAAAAUGAAAGAGGGUAGGGGGGAUUAGAAUGUGGUGGUCAGCCCCUGGAGUGUGGCUUGUGGGCUGCUUCUUGUCCUGUAGUAUUUCCUCUUUGGCUGGUUUUCCAGGGAGAGCUUUUCAGUCUCCCAAUGUCCCACCUGGGGCUCCAGGUCUGACUGCCAGCGUUCCAGGAGCCACGUGGAGAGAAGAGGGCUGGGUGCUGGCCUGCAGUGUUGGUUCCUGCCCCAGCCUGUUCAGAGAAGGCUGAGACAGGGAUCAGGGAGGCUGUGGGGGGCGUCUAACUGCCUCUGCUUCCCAGUCACCUCCCCAUGCUUAUAUCUUAAGCUCCUGUCAACCCCCCGGUUUCGGACAUAUCUGGUGGGACUCGUUUCAGAGCCUUUCAAGGCUUCUGUAGGAGCCACUGUGUUGGUGCUCAGCUUUUCUGCUGAAGGCCUGGGAUUUGGCUUUGCUGAAUGUGUGAAAUUACUCACUUCUUCUUCAUCAGCUUUUUUGCCUCCUUACCUUUGUGUGCUGAGUGGGUGUGUCUUUUUUAAAAAAAGUCUCUGGACUGUAGUUUUGGUUAGAGUUUAGGAGGAGGUGAAAUGAAUGUGGGUUUUCAGCCUGCUGUUUUAACCUGGCACUGCUGUUGAAAAGAAUCUUGUUGUUUGGACUCUAGGGUACGAUCAAGCUGCCACAUCCUUCCUGGACAUGCUGAGCCUGGGGAGAUUUUUCACUCGCUCCCCUGUGCAGUGUCUCCUUCCGUGCCCCUCCUUGCUGUACCAGGAGGUGCACUUGUUAUGUUUCUGUAACGCCCUUUGUACCUUGAUAUGGUUUGGCUCUGUGUCCCCACCCAAAUCUCAUCUUGUAGCUCCCAGAAUUCCCACAUGUUGUGGGAGGGACCCGGUGGGAAAUAACUGAAUCAUGGGGGUGGGUCUUUCCCAUGCUGUUCUCGUGAUAGUGAAUAAGUCUCACGAGAUCUGAUGGUUUUAAAAAUGGGAGUUUCCCUGCAGAAGCUCUCUUCUCUUGUCUGCUGCCAUGUGAGACGUGCCUUUCAUUUUCCACUAUGAUUGUGAGACCUCCCCAGCCAUGUGGAGCUAUAAGUCUAAUAAGCCUCUUUCUUUAGUAAAUUGCCCAGUCUCGGGUACAUCUUUAUCAGUGAAAAUGGACUAAUGCAUACCUAUUUUGUUCUGUUAAAGUCCUACUCAUCUUUCAUUUUCAAAUAUAGAUUCCCCAAAGGAAUCCUUCCCUGGACCCCUGACCCUGGCCCAGAUGAACUUGAGCCUCUGUUGGUGUCCUUCAGCAGCUUGUUCUGUCACAGUUAUGCUUAAUCAUUUGUGCAGCUCCUUGUAUAAUACCGGCCUCUUUUUGCCUAACUUUGAAGCUCCAGGAAGGCAAGGACUGUGUCUUUCCUGUCCAUUCUUAGAAACAUACUUUCUUGACCAUAGUAGCACUCAUUAAAUACCUGUCCAAUAAAUGCGUGAAUUCAUGGACAUAUGUCUUCAACUCCUUGAAUUUAAUUUUUUUUUUUUUUUUUUUUGGAGGCAAUCUUGCCCUGUCACCCAGGCUGGAGUGCAGUGGCAUGAUCUCAGCUUGGCCCCCUGCAACCUCUGCCUCCUGGGUUCAAGAGAUUCUCCUGCCUCAGCCUCUCAAGUAGCUGGGAUUACAGGCAUGCACCACCAGGCCCAGCUAAUGUUUUUUGUAUUUUUAGUAGAGCUGGGGUUUCACCAUGUUCGCCAGGCUGGUCUUGAACUCCUGAACUCAAGCAAUCCACCCACCUCGGCCUCCCAAAGUGCUGGAUUUAUAGGCGUGAGCCACCAUGCCUGGCCUGAAUUUAAAAUUUUUGAGUUCAUAUAUAGAUUAAAUGGACAUGCACACUUUUUUAGAGGUAUGAAUACUAAGACUCAAAAGGUAUACACAUUAAUCAUUCUAAUAUAUUUGUAAUUAAAAAUUAACUAAUUCAUUAAACAUUUAUUGUCUUUGCACAAAGCUAUUAUGUGCUGUUGACCUGAUUCCAGAGUUUAAUAGUUUGUUCAUAUUUUCCAAAAUACAAUUACCUUACCUUCUUCCCUCACUUUAAUUUCUUCCCAUAAGAAUUCAGACUAUUAUUUUGGUAGGGUAUGUGAGCAUUAUCAUCUUAUUCAGUAUUUUGUGCAUAAUUAAGGAGUGCUUUAAGAGCAGAUACUGAAUAUUACUUUUGGGCCUCUCAUGAGGCAGGGUGUGGGGUUAGGCACUUUAUAAAUAGACAUUAGUUGCAUUGAAUAUUAUGUGUUCUUAAAGCUGGUGAGAUACUUUCAUUAAUGUUUUCUCUUAUUUCAGUUCAAUGGAAGAGACACAGGAGGUUUCUUAACUAUAUUUUGUAAUGAGUGAGAAUCUACACGUUUAAUUUGGAGGGUGUGAGAACAUCAUUUUCUUAGUUUGCAAAGGCUACUGUCACAAAUUCCCAUGGACUGGAUGACUUAGAAUGACAGAAAUUUGUUCUCUCAUGCUUCUGGAGACUAGUGUGUGAAAUCAGGGUGUCGGCAGGACCACACUCCCCUGAAGGCUCUGGGUGGAAGCAGAGGGCGGCCCUGGCUUCUGGGGUCGCCUGUGUCCUGGGCUUUGCUUGGUCUGUGGCCACCUCCCUCGGUUCCCUGCCUCCAGGUUCACAUGGCCUUCUCCACAUCUGUUCAAAUUUCUCUCUGCUUACAAGACAACCGUCAUUUGACUGGCCCUGUGUGAAUCCCAUCCAACUUUGUCUUAACUCAAUUGCAGUUACAAAGACCCUAUUUUCAAAUAAGGUUGCAUGAUAGCUUCUGGGUGAGUAUGAAUUUGCAGGGAGACACUCUUCAACCCAAUCUGAUCGCAUUUCAUGUAUGUACAGAAAUCUUAGAAAUAACACAGUGGCACUCUCUACUGACUUCCUCUGCUUACACGAAGGUAAUGUUCAGAGAAAUGGUAUGGAUGCAUGGGAUGAGGAUCCAACUGUCUUAGCAGUUGCUUCAUUUAUUUAAAAAAAAAAAAAGAGAAAUCUUCUCUCAAGUUUUUAGAAGUUCUAGCAAGCAGUAUUCUUUGUGCAGGAUCCAAAAAGAGACACACACACACACACACACACACACACACACACACACACACACGCACACACUUACUUGCUUUUUUUCUCUGUUAUCACUGUUGAUCAUCACUGUUUCUCAGCAGGCAGACUUUUUUCUAGUUUCUUUCAUUACGGUAAAAGGAAUAUGUGUUUGAAUUCAGCAGUGAGUCAUCUGAGAUGCGUGUUGUUAUGGAAAAUUGCCAUAGCGUUCAGCUGUUACGAGACAGAAGUCAAAGCUAAGCACAUUUAAUGGCCGGAGAUGAGCGGUAUUUCCAAGAAGUUCUUUUUAUUAUUUUUACACUUUAGAUGAAAUGGGUAUUUGGAUGGGAUGAGUCCCAUUAUGCUGCGGUUGCUCACGUUGGGGGGAUGUGUUCACACGUCUGUGUGGUUGUCGGUGUCUGUGCAUGCAAUGUGAUUGAGCUCCUGGGUAGGUGUUCCUUUCUGUCUUGAAUACAAACUGGAACAGUAUGAGAACAAGCUCAUGAUUAUUAUUUCUACUGUUAUUUAUCUUUGAUUUAAGAGAUCACUGUGAAUAGCUUUGGAUGCCAUACUUUACUGGGAAUUCUGACUUACCUUAUUUGGCAAAUACAGAUCAUUUCCAAAAUGUACAUUCAGUUGAAGGAUAAAUAGUUGAUGAAAUAGGUUUAAAAAAACUCAAAGGACAUUAAAAGCCUCAUUUUAUUGAAAAAUAAAUAAUGACUUUUUUUUUCUUGAAGACGAACCCUGUUAUUUAGAGGCCUAAAAGAUUUGCCAAAACUAUCCAUAUACUAUCCAUGUCUAUAACAAGUCUGUAGAGGUGACUGCACUGUAUAUCACCGUGGCUCUCAGUGGAUUUUAAUUUAGAGCAGAUGUCUCUGCAUCACACAGCUGGGUGAGUCUCAGCUUUUGGAACACAAAGAAAUCUUCCUUUUAAAAAUCAACUUAAGAUAUGUUUAGAAAGUAGAUAAAGGCCAGGUGCGGUGGCUUAUGCCUGUAAUCGCAGCACUUUGGGAGGCCGAGGUGGGUGAAUCACCUGAGGUCAGGAGUUUGAGACCAGCCUGGCCAACAUGGCGAAACCCUUUCUCUAUUAAAAAUACAAAAAUUAGCUGGGCGUGGUGGUGGGCACCUGUGAUCCCAGCUACUCGGGAGGCUGAGGCAGAAGAAUCACUUGAACCCAAGAGGUGGAGAUUGCAGUGAGCCGAGAUCGUGCCACUGCACUCCAGCCUGGGCGACAGAGCGAGACUCUGUCUCAAAAAAAAAAAAAUUAGAUAAAACCUUUCUUUGACAUAGUCACUUUGACCAAUUUUGCAGCCUCUGGAAACCAUCAUUUGAUUAACUUAUGACAUAUCCCAAUGUCCACUCAAGCAAAACGCCCCAGUUUCCAUAAAAGCUUUUUAUUUUUGUCUUUUGCGAAGGACUACUAGGAAGGGUUUCUGUCAGUUUGUUUCUGUCAUCAAACAAUGAAGUUUAUUACAGGACAGACUCAGUCUUUUGGUCAAUAAUGUCUUUGUUGCCUCAGUUUUCCAGUUCACUGAGUGUAUACUAAGAGACCACUAAAGGAUUUUUUGGGGCUUGGUAAGUUUUAAAACUAGGGCUAGAGGAGACUAGAAAAUAAAAGCCUAUCAGUAAUUGUAACAUGUCACGUGUCUGACAUUUACGAGCCUCCAUAUUACUUUUUCGUUCCCAGCAAUUCUUAUAAAUCGUAUUCCAUAUCUGAGAUCCUACGUGUUUGCAAAUAUUAAAUUGUACAAGUUUCACUGACAACUCAUUUGUCCACCAAAAAGAUCUAUAAAUAAGAAACAGCAAUUCCCAAUUUUCUAGUUAAUGGAAAUAAAAUAUUGUUUCCUUAGAGGAAUACAGAAAUAUAGCUGGGAGAAGACAGAAGCUCUCUAGCUUACUUUGUUCAUGACCACACCUUGUCACAGCAAGGAAGGGACAUACCUGAAAUGUCACUAACAUCUAUGAUCCUUUUUUUAUCCUUUAAAGAAGGGAAAUUGUUGGAACUUUUUUGUGUUCUUUAAAAAAAUAUUGAAAAUCUCAGUGUGUUUGAAAUUCUAAAUGAGCUACUCAGAGAUUUGCCUUAGAGUGCAGGGAAUUAUGCAUAAGACAACUGCACUUCUUUGGGAGGCUGAGGCUGGCAGAUCUACUUGAGGUCAGGAGUUCUAGACCAGCCUGGCCAACAUGGUGAAACCACAUCUCUACUAAAAAUGCAAAAAUUAGCCAGAAGUCACUUGAACCCGAGAGGCGGAGGUUGCAGUGAGCUGAGAUCUUGCUACUGCACUUCAGCCUGGGCAACAGAGUGAGACUCCAUCUCAAACAAACAAACAGAAAGACAACUGCACUUGAGUCCAAAGCCUUGGCAUCCUCCUUGUAGCCUCUCUCCGCUUCACACCUCUGUGUUGGGGAUCCCCACAUCUGCCCCAGGUUUGGUAAUUUACUGAAAGGACUCACAGGAUUCAGAAGUCAUUACACUCAUGGUUAUAGGUUAUUACAGUGAAAGGAUAGAAAGCAGAAUCAGCAAUGGGGUGAAGUCCAGAAAACCAGACAGAAGCUUCCAGAGCCCCCUCCUGGAGGCGUCACACAGCACCCAGCUGUGACAAGAGGUGCCAGGUACUCUUCUACCAGGGCAGUUCCUUAGACACUCAGUGCUCAGGGUUUUUACUGGGGACUGGUCACAUAGGAACCCUCUGCCUGGCACAGACCAGAAUUCCCAACUCUUAGAAGGAAACCAUAAACCAGAUUGUUUGUACACACAGUUUAGACACAGCAAACCACUCUUAUAUUUAGGAAAAGUUUUAGAUUGGUAUAAGCUAUUUUUUAUCAGCCACAUUUCCAGAUUGCAGCCACAGACCCCCCCUUGCAGGCGAGCCCCCUCUGUGAGGACCACAGCCUAGGCCUCCCAGGUGAACCCUUCUCUGCACACUUCCAUUCCACCCAUCAGGAAAUUUUGUUGGCUCUCCCUUCAAACUCUGUCCUGAACUCACUCUUCUGUGUAGCCUUUGCCACUGCCCAAGUCCAGGCCACCAUCUCUGUCCCAUGGACUGUCCCAUCACGCCAGAGCUUGUUUCCUGGCUUCUAGUCAUUGCGUCCCCCGACUGCAGCCAGAGGGCUUCUGUUGAAACUGAAGUCAGAUGGAGCCCCACUUUUGCUCCUGCCUCCCUGUGGCAUGUCAUCUCAUCAGGGCGGGAUGCCUGGGUCCAGUCGCCUGAUGCUGGAGGCUUCACGUACCUGCCGUGCCCCCUCCAGCUCCCCACUAUCCCACUGACACCUGCUUACUCCUGCCUAAGGCCUUUGUAUAAUGCCUGGUCUGCCUGGAAGGUCACCCCCAGAUUCCUGCAUGGCCCCUUCCCUCACUUCCUACGGGUGUCUGCUUAAAAUUAGAAAACCCUGGACUGGGCGUGGUGGCUCAUGCCUGUAAUCCCAGCAGUUUGGGAGGCCGAGGUGGGUGGAUCACCUGAGGUCAGGAGUUCGAGACCAGCCUGGCCAACAUGGUGAAACCCCAUCUCUACUAAAAAUACAAAAAUUAUCUGGGCAUGGUGGUGCUUGCCUAUAAUCCCAGCUACUAGGGUGGCUGAGGCAGGAGAAUCGCUUGAACCCGGGAGGCGGAGGUUGCAGUGAGCUGAGAUCAUGCUAUUGCACUCCAGCCUGGGUGACAGAGCAAGACUCUGUCUCAAAGAAAAAAAAAAAGGAAAGAAAACCGCACUCUGUUCCACUAUCUCCCCUUCUGCGCACUCUCCCUGCUAUCCUGGUUCAGCACUGAUCUCAGCACUGAUUCCCCCGACUAUUAUAUAGCACUUUGCCUUUUAUUUUUUAAAUUUAAUUUAAAUAGUUUUUUGCAUUUGGCCUCCUUCCCCUAGCUAGAAUGCAGGCUCUGCGAGAGCCAAGUUUGUAUUUCCAUGACUGCUUUAUCCUCAGUGCCUUCCGCAGUACCCAGGACAUCAUCAGUUCUCAGUAAAUGUUCUUGAAUGGGGAUUCAUGGGGAUAUAAGUCCAAAAAUUAACUUAGAAGGAUCAAAACAUAGGAGAGGUCAUCACUAUAACUUAAAUUAAGCAAGCCUCCUGUGAGUAGUUCUGAAUAAUAGAGAUGACUAGCCUAAGAGGGGAAUGGCUCCAUUUAUGGGAUGGUGAGUUUACAACUAAGGAUGGCACUUUUGUAAUCAACUAAAAAUACCCCAGCUCAGUUCUUUGCUAAGAAGAGGAAAGAGUUGAGAGCACUGAGAAGAGUAUUUGGCCUCCCAAUUAAUUUCAAUUCCUCAUUGAAAUUAAGAAGACAUCUCAGGGGCCAGGCGCGGUGGCUCAUGCCUGUAACCUCAGCACUUUGAGAGGCCAGGCGGGAGGAUUGCAUGAACUCAGGAUUUCUAGACCAGCCUGGGCAACAUGGUGAAACCCCAUCUCUACACAAUAUACAAAAAUUAGUCGGGCGUGGUGGCAUGCGCAUGUUAUCCCAGCUACAUGGGAGGCUGAAGCAGGAGAAUCACUUGAACCCGGGAGGCGGAGGUUGCAGUGAGCUGAGAUUGUGCCACUGCACUCCAGUCUGGGAGACAGAGCGAGACUUCAUCUCAGAGAAGGAAGGAAGGGAGGGAGGAAGAGAGGGAGGCAGGGGAGGGAGGGAAGGAGGGAGGGAGGGAAGGAGGGAGGGAGGGAGAUCUCAGCAUUAAAAAAGAAAUCAAAACAUAAAAUUAAAAUCUCAGCAUUAAAAAAACAAAACAAAAACAAAUCAUGUUCCACGAAAUCCUGUUGCUCACAAACCUGAAAUGUCAAGGUUUGCUGCUUGUUGAAAGUGAUCACGGACUAGGCUUAAUGUCUACACAUGUUUUAUGUAAGUUUUUUUUUUUUUUUUUUUCCUCUUUUUUAAAAUGUCCGUCUUUUCAGAUUGUUUGAUCCAGGCACUAACCUGCUACUGUAUACUGUUUUCUAACUAAACAAAUAGAGAAUAAAGAUAUAAGGAACUUGAGGAAUAAGCCCAAGAGAGCACUGUGGUCUGGGGAUACGGUUGGCAUCCAGGGUUUCUGCUUUUUUAUAGGCAGCUAAUUCUUUUCUGCUGAAUUGAUCGCUGUUUCAUGUCAUGCUUCUCAGGAGUGUAUGUAGCUGACGGGUGAGGUGCGGCUGGGCAGUGACUCCCUAGUGCUUCCUGCUUAUUUCCGUUUUAUUUGAAGCCAAGGAGGAGUUUGUUUUUGAUGUGAGUCAUAUGCCCAGGACACUAAUUCCAAUCCAUUCUCUUAUCACCUCCCUGACCAGUUCCUAAUCAGAAUCUGUACCUCAUGGAGGUUACAGGGAUCCAAGGUCAUGAUAACUGAGGCUUGUACUGCAUCUGGACUCAGAACAGAGCAAAUGUGUGCCUGGUCUAAGUACUUCCGUAAAAUACCCAGUGUCUUGGUGUCCUUCUGCAGCACAGUCUCUGUCGUCUUUGACAUAAGUAUCGAGAUUAUACACACAUCACUGAUAAGGGAUAAAAGGCACCCUGGAAAUCCGUAAAUAAAGGACUAGCAGUCACGGCAGUGCACUGCAUUGAGUCUGGUUUGGUUGGGUCUGAAACUGUACCUGAAAUGGUUUCUUUAAGUAUCUUGCUUUCUCUAUUUCUCGAUGUUUAAUAAAGGAAGGGACACGGACAUGUAGAGAAGGCUAAAAUAAGAAAUGCUGUGUGAGGCCAUUUUUCCCCACACAAACCAAGAAAGAAAUAAAGACCUUCCCUGCAUGGACACCCUCUCUACUAAGAGUGUUCAUGCUGCUCAUAGCACUGAAGAUUCCACAUCCAGUGCUUUUUUUCAGUGUUUUCUUAGCUUUCAAUGAUGUACCUGUCAGUGUGAUUAUAGAUUUAACCCUUAGGAGGGAAUCUCUCCUACAUUUUAGCAUCGGAGACCUAGAUUAAAGGCUGAGGAGAGAAGAUUAAAUGUGGCCAAGAGAGAGAAGCUUUUCUUUCUCAUUCCGUCUGGUACAGCCAAAGGGGUAAGGAAGACGCGGGCUUCUCUUACGAUAGAUUGUGAGGCUGCAGUUUCUAUGGUGACUGGUUUCUUUUUCCCUUAUUCAGCAGCUAAAUGCAGCAACAUUCAAACACUUGUAGCUGAGUUUGGCCUUCAGGUGGGACACUUACAUUCUCCAGGCAUUUGCCUUAAGCCCAUAUAUAGAGACAGAGCUUAAUUUUUUCCCCAAGUCAUUUAGCAGUUAAUGUUUGUGGGAUACAUGAUGGAUAUCUCCUUCUCAUCAUGUUAUCCCCAAAUGGCUUUGAAAUAGAGGCUGUUGGCCGGGCACGGUGGCUCACACCUGUAAUCCCAGCACUUUGGGAAACCAAGGCGGGUGGAUCACCUGAGGUCAGGAGUUCGAGACCAGCCUGGCUAACAUGGUGAAACCCUGUCUCUACUAAAAAUACAAAAAUUUCCUGGGCAUUAGUGGCACGUGCCUGUAGUCCACCUACUCGGGAGGUUGAGGCAGGAGAAUCACUUGAACCCGGGAGGUGGAGUUUGAAGUAAGCUGAGAUCGCGCCAUUGUACUCCAGCCUGGGCGACGAGGGAGAAACUCUGUCUCAAAAAAGAAAAGAAAAGAAAAGAAAAGAAAUAGAGGCUGUUUUGAUGGUAGGUGAUUUUGUUAGCAGACUGGUGCAUGUCCCUCUGUGAUCUCGGUGCCAUUGAUUGAACUUGGGAGGUUUCUACCCCAUGGCUGGAGCCGGGUCUGUUCUCUCAGGCAUCCCCAGUGUCUGGGCCUGAAAGCAUGGUUCUGCAGAGUACGUGCUCCCCUACCUCCUGUUGCCAUUCCCGUUUCUUUACAGACUUGAAGAGGUUUGUUAAACAGAAUCUCUUUGGGUGGAAAACCCCAGAGAAGUCCAGUUCGUUGAAUACCCGUCCCUGGCAACAUACAGAACUGCGAGGUGGGGUUCAUCUGUGGGAUCCUUUGCCUGUUCUGGGUACUUGAACUGAAGCACAUGAAUUCCAUGGCAAAAAAGGACCAGCGGGGCCAUCUAGUUUUUAUGAGUAUUGGAGAAAAUCUUAUAAGAGACACACUAAAGAGGGCAACAUUGGUCAAACAAUAAAUGUAACUAUAAAAAUCGCAAAAUCCAGAUCUAUACAGAGUUCGCCAUCGCAGCUGCUUGAUCACUGGGGCCUGAGCUCCGCUGUCUGCAGUCCGUUAGAUAGCAACUUGCUUUUAAUCCUAAACGUUAAGAAUUUAAGAAUUUAGUCAACUUUCAGUUAUCUGCUCCGGGAGUUCUCACUCCCAAAUGGCUUCUGCUUACCGCGGAUAAUUCUGGCUCUUGCCAGUUCCCGGGGAACUUGCAGGGAGGGUGAGAUCAUAUUAGCAUGAACUUAGCGUAAUUGGUGUAUGGGAUUUGGAGGUGUGCAAAGGGGAUACAUCUCUUGUUUAUAAAACUAGACACAUUUCAAAGUGAUCAUUGUGCCUGAUUUUUUAUUUUUUGGGCCAUUUUCUAUUCCAUUCUCUAUUAAUAAAAAUAAUUAAGAAAAGAUUAUAAUUCUUUUAUCUACAGAAGAUCUUAUUGUGGAUUUAAGCCACGGUAAAAUUGUUUGGAGGUGGCUCCCCCAUCCCCCCUCCAAAAAACAUUAAAAAACCACCAAUCCUUUUGCAAGUUAGGCCACCCGUUUAAGCCCCGUAGUGCCUUUCAUGAACAGACACUUGCUCCAGGGAGAAACCUGAUGUAAAGAGAAGUUUGAGCUUCUCUCUUUUAACUUUAGGACUUCAGAGGUUUGAGAGCUAAUGGAAAAUGAGGACCCCAUGUAAUAAGGGGAGCCCAGUGGUGUGGCCAUGCCACCGGGCCUUGCCCUUCAGCGCUGUCACCCCUGCCCCCAGGGAGGGCACACUGAGGAGGCUGGCCUACUUUGCUGGGUGUCAAUAAAAGGUGUGGGGACUGUUCAUUCCUGAGCUUUCUCUCUUCCGUCCUUCCGCCAGCCACCCUACUUUGAAUCUGCCUGUCUCAAUGACAUAAAGUCAAGGAUAAGAUAAAAUCUGCCUCCAGUUUUGUCGCCAGUGCCAUUUAUAACCAGAAAGGCCAGCACGAACAUGUCAGAUAAACCUUUACAUGAAUAUAUGAUGUCCUGCACUUAACAACUUGAUGAAAGGAAAGGCUCAGUUUAGGAGAGUGGAAACCUGCUUUAAAGCUCCUUAAUAUUUAACAAGAUCUUGCACUUGUGGUGACCUGCAAAGUCUCUAGAUCACAACAGGAUUUAUUCUUUUCCCUGCCGGCAUCUGGAUUCUCCUAAAAGUAAAUCCAUCCAGACAUGCCUGCAUACGUAACCCCCACCCGGCAAAGGGAUCAGAACAUUUGGUCAUUUCGCCUGUGAGUCUGUACUGAUUCAUGCACUCCCUGAUCCUCAGUCAUUGCUGAGCAUCCGAAGAUUCUGAGAGACUGCAGGUCUAUAAACAAUGGGACAGGGAGCCAAGGCAUGGCCAGAGUGUUACAAACCCUGGCUUUCUGUGUGAUAAGCCACUCACCUUGAGGACGUUUUUGGAAUAUGCAUUAACCUUUCAGACCUUUCGGGAUAGCAUAAAAAGGUACGAAGGAAAAACAUAAUUGAAGCCAUAGAUGAAUCAUAGGAACUCAAAAACCAUUCUUCAUUGGAAAGUGUUGCAGUGAAUUGGUGAGCGUUUCUAGUGAUUCGCACCCACGGGCUGCAGACCUUGUGCUGGGUACUGUGCAUAUACUAUCUCACAUCCCCACAGUAACCUGACUCGAGAGGCACAGGAGUCUUACUGGUUAAGUUCAGGAAUUGCCAGGCUCAGAGAAGUUAAUUUCUAGUCAUACCUCAUACAGAGAGACCAUGGGUGAGCCAGGAUGCACAGACGUACCUCAAACCCAAGGCCACACUUUUUUUUUUUUAAUGUUUCUUUGUUAAACUGGGGUAUUUAAAGACUGCGCAAACUCAGUAUUAUUAUAACAAAGAACCAGAAAAUGAAUUCUGAGAGUAUUCAGUGUUGCCUAUUCAGUAUGGUAUUUGAACUGGAGUAUGUUGCUCAACUCCUUAUUACUCAGUUGCUUUUGACGAGGGCUCUCCUGGGAUUUUGGCCAGGAUGAUUUUUUUAUUGUACUAAGUGACAACUGCCCCUGCCCCUUGCCAAAUAACUGUCUGCACUGGGGAAUGUGGUAGAUGCCGCCUGUGUAGAAUUAGAACCAGUGGUGUAAGCCGGAAGAGUGGCCCCAUUUUUCUUGUCAGUGAUUGGCUUAGGGAGAGAUUUGUGACCAAUUUGGGUCAGUAAUAAAUGAGGACAUCUGCUGGUAGUUUCUGGAAUAGGUUUCCUUGCUUUGAAGAAGCAGCAUAGGGAAGAGGGGGCCUUGCUCUGCCUGAGAGGCCUGGAGUUUCUGCAGCCAUCUUGAGCCCACAAGGGAGGAGCUGGACUGGGGAAAGCUGUCAUAUUUAGGGUGUGGAAGGAGGAGGAUGAAAAGAACCGAGGCCAUUUCUGACAUUGCUCAUGGCUCUGUUCACCAGGCUUUUCUAUUCACUUGCCUUUUCUCUGGACCCCUUUGCUGUGUGAGAUAAUGGAUUUCCUUAUGGUUUAUACCAGGUCGAGUAGGGUUUUCUGUCUGGUCUUUGUGUGAGAAGGCCCUUUAAUAGAUAAAGGCUUCCUUGGGGACCAGUACCAUUUCAGGUGACUGGUCUGCUUGUCUGUAGGUUGGAAAUGAUUGCUUACUCCUUGCAAACAGAGAACCCAUUGCUGCCAUAGUGGUAGUAGGCAGUGGGUUAAGGAGUACUUGAGUUAUUGUUAUUGUCCUGUGCAUGCAAAGCACCUCUUGUACCACCAUAUUGUGGUCACCAUUGUUUAUGGUUAUUGCUGUCAUUCAUAACAGCAUCUUUGAAUCUUAUACACUAGACAUUCAAAGUGGAGGCAGUGGGAGGGUAACAGCAGCACCAGGUCUGCAGUGUAGACUGGCAGCACCGGGUCUGCAGUGUAGACUGGCACAAAUGUAAGUGUGAAUUUCCAGUUCUUGCUGAGACAGCAUCAGAGUGAGUCAAAAUUAACAGGGUUGGUUGGCACUGCUGAUCACACCAAGGGGCUGAAGGGUGGGUACUAGAGUGAGUUAAUGCUGGAGACAGAGGCAGAGAGAAUCCACUGAUGCUGAGGAAGCUCAUCAGAAGUGUAGGGGGAGGAGACCACAAGGUCAGGUGUCUCAUCAGCGAUACCUGACUUCUCUCUUAACCGAAUCUGAAUCAGUGGUCCUCAACUCAGGGGCCAGGGGCAUGUGCCCUUCAGUGGACAUGUGGCAAAGCCAGGAGACAUUUCAGUUGUCCCAGGUGGGGGAUGCAGUCAGCAUCUAGUGGAUAGACCCCAGAGAUGCAGUUGCAACAUCCUACAGUGGCAGAACAGCCCCCCAACAAAGAUUCUGGCCCCCAAAGGCCAAUAGUGUUGAGGCUGACCAUCCCUGUUUCUCACCUGGAAGUGGUUGAUGGAGGGAGCCGAGGGCAGCUGGGGUGUGAGGAAGGCUCUGGAGACUGAAGCUGUUAUUAGAUCCAGUCCAGGCUGCUUGGCAGUGGGCACUUUCCAGUGGGGAGGCUUCCCACUUGUGGCAGAGCACGUAGAGGGGUUUGCAAGCUCUCUGUGUUUACUGGCCUCCACGUUGGUGUCUGGGAAGGGCAAAACAGAAGCUCAGACUGCUGGGUGGAGAAGUUUUGCGCCUUCCCAGCUCUUGCUUCUUUCUGUGAAGCAUGCUGGCGUCAUGUUUCCAUGACAGCAGUUGAGUUAAUGCAUUUAGGGGCCCCCUCAGCGUCCACCACAUCCUGCCUGUUGUAAAUUGUGUGGUUCAGGUUGUGAUCUAUGAUACUACGGUCCUAAAUUUCUCAUUACUAUUUUUUAACUUGAUUGAAUGCACAGCUACUAGACAAAAUCGCUCUUUACCUCUGUAAGUAAAAAAUAGAAAUGCUUAUUAGUGUUCAGCAAUAGAUUUUAAAAUUACAUUUUUGUUACAAAUACUUCACUGGCUAAAUUGAAAUCAGUGUGAUCAAAUUGAAAUGUCAUAAUACUAUUGAUUUAAUAAAUGCUGGCCUCCUAAUAUCUGUUUUUCAAUGAAACUAGUAUUACGGGAGUAAUUUUCUAAUGAACAUCUGAGCACUAGGUCAUUGGUAAAACAAAAGAAGAAUGAUAUCAUAAAUGGUUCUGGAUGGUUUUUUCAGCGGGACCUGGCAUGCUGAUACGAAUAGAGGAAUUAAAGCGUAGCUCAUUAUAUAUUAAUUUGAAUGUAAUACUAACUAAAACCUUCCAUUGACUUCACUGAAGCCUAGUCUUAGAAAUUAUGCAGAUUAAUGGAGGCCUUGAAAAGAAGCACAUGCAAUAUUUGAGUUCCCUUUGGACCAAAAAACUGGCAUGUUGGAACUGAAAAAAUUAUAUACUGUGCAGUAUUUUUGUGUAAGUACAAUACACUAAAAGAUUUUGUUGCUUAAAAAAACUGGGCAGGGUGAAUCCUAUAUCUGUUUUUUGUCUAUUUUAUUUUAUAUCCAAAUAAGCCGAAAGGAAGAAGCAAAGGACCGAAGGUUGACACUGAGAUUGCUGCUGCAGAGGGAGAAUUUCCUGCAGCUUUUGAUUGUGGAACUCAGGUUAAGAAUGUGGUUCCUGGAGCCAGGCACGGUGGCUCACGCCUGUAAUCCCAGCACUUUGGGAUGCUGAGGCGGUUGGAUUGCUUGAACCCAGGAGUUUGAGACCAGCCUGAGCAACAUGGCAAAACCCCAUCUCUACAAAAAAUACAAAAAAUUAGCCAGGUAUGGUGGUGCACACCUGUCGUCCCAGCUACCCGGGAGGCUGAGGUGGAAGUAUUGCUGGAGCCUGGGAGGCGGAGGUUGCAGCAAGCCUUGAUUGCAUCAUUGCACUUCAGCCCGGGUGGCAGAGACCCUACCUCAAUGAAAAAAGAAUUUGGUUUCUGCAUAAGGAUGAUUUCACUGCCUUUUUUGUUUUUACAUGAAAAUCCUCACCAAGUACAUUUUAAUUUUGUUGUAUUAAUUAAUGAGAACUUGUUCUCCCCUGUGCCUCAUCUUUCACAAUUUUAUAUCAUGUGAGAUGUAUUUAUCUAAUAAAGUGGCGAUGGGAAGAGGCAUUAGCUAUUUUCGGAGUCUGUGAUAGCCACAUAGUGACAUUUUAAAAGCAUAAGCUUCGGUUCUUCAAGCCCCUCAAGUAAAUGUGGAGAUGAGUCAAGUUCAGGCAGGCCCAGCAGACAUGAAUGUUCUUUCUUUUCUGUCUUCUCUUUCUCCUGUCUCUCUGUUAGUAAUACUCUCCAUUGCUGUCUGUAGAUUAAUACUCACAGCCACGUGUAUACUGUAUUUUAUAAAGAACUUUGCUGUUCACCCUGAAGCUUUGGCACCUGCCAGAGACAUGAGUUGCUGCUGACUCAUGAUGACUAUAUCCAGGCAGGUGUGUUUCUCCCGCAGCGAUGGUUCACUCCUCCUGAAUCAGGUGCUGUCCCUUUCCAGGCACAGCAACCACUGGCAAGGCAGGGACUUCAUCAGAGGCAGAUGUUGAAAGUGGUGGGUGACCGUGGGUAGUGAGUGCACCCAGGGCAGGCUCUGACGUUGUGGGAUCCUCCUGACCCCUGUUUUAAGUGAAAAAAGUGAGACAUAAGCCAAAACUAUAAAGUCAGGACACCAAGAUAUUGCAGUUUGUCCAUACUCCUUUUUCCAGCGUGAUACUCUACUUCCUGUUUCUCACUGUACAGUUUUUUCUUUUCUUUUCUUUCCCCUCCCCUCCCCUCCCCUCCCCUUCCCUUUCCAACGGAGUCUCGCUCUGUCACCCAGGCUGGAGUGCAGUGGCGUGAUCUCUGCUCACUGUAACUUCUGCCUCCGGAGUUCAAGCCAUUCCCCUGCCUCAGCCUCCGCAGUAGCUGGGAUUACAGGCGCCCACCGCCACGCCCAGCUAAUUUUUAUAUUUUUAGUAGAGAUGGGGUUUCAUAAUGUAGGCCAGGCUGCUCUCAAACUCCUGACCUCAGUGAUUUUCUAAGUAAAUUUCCAGCUUCUCAGGGUCAGCAAUCACAUCAACUACUUUCCUGUGCGUCCAUCAUAGGAUGGUGCCUGUCACAUAGUGUUUAAAAUACCAGUCCCAGGCUGGGGUUGGUGUGGACUUUGCAGCCAGCCACGUGUACUAGAUUAACCACGUUGGUCAGAGUAACCUGUCUUGGUUAACAUCGAUAACAUCGCAUGGAAGUCGGUAUCGAUGGAGGAUAAUUGAUGAAGCACUGUGGACAUUUUGCUGCACAUAUUUCCUAAAUCUUCAUUGCUUACUGUAUAAACACACAAAAGUAGUCAUGGUAUUUGUUAAUUGUUGAUGAAGGUUGUGACUGGCUGUAGGUAAACAUUUUGGAAGUAAUUUUUAGGACUGGAAUGCACUCACAUGCUUUUUUCUUAAGCCACUGAAAAGUGCGAGGAAUUAACAGCAAAACUUGGAGGUUUUAAGUAAAUGAUCAGUGUUAGUAGCUAUCACUUUUUAACUUAGCAAUAGCUCUCUUUGAAAGAAAAUUCUAGGGGGCUUUAAGUAGGUUGUAGGUUGUAGUGGUAUUGUUUGCUUGUACUAAUUAUUGAUUUUUUAAAAAUCCUUUUUGGUCUUUGUUCCGUGGUCUGUUAUAUAACCUGGUGGCUAGAGGGUGGGCUCAGACUGAAUCAGGCUGCUUGGGUUUGAAGCCUGGCUUCUCUUGGUAGCUGUGUGCCCUUGCUUAGAUAACUUCAUCUCUCUAAAUCUUAAUUUCCUCCCACAAGAGGGAUUCCACCCCACAGUCUGUGUCAGCAGAAAAUGACAAUGCAGGGAGCAUGCCUGCCAGUAUUUACAACAUGUUAGCUGUUUCUGUCCACUUGAUAUUACAGCCUGAGCAUCUCUUAUCCAAAAUGCCUGGGACCAGACGUGUCUCUGGGUUCAGAUUUUGGAAUAUUUGCAGUACAUUUGUCUGUUGAGCAUCUGAAAACCUGAAAUCGAAAAGGCUCCAAUGAGCAUCUCAUGUGAGCAUCUUGUUGGCCCUCAAAAAGUUUCAGGUUUGGGGCUUGGGAUUUUCAGAGUUGGGAUUCCAGUUUGUAUACACAGAACCUAGUUAGUCUCAGCACAGAGUUACUACAUCUUAGUAGGAGAGUGAGAACUGCUCAGGCUCUGGAGGGAAUAAAGCUGAUGAAACCAGGGUGCAGAAAGGAAGUUGAUGUAGAUAGAACCACUUUUACCACGUCAGUCUGCUGAAAAUAAGGUUCCCUGAAGAGACAUUGCCACAGUAGCCUGUGAAGACAGUCUUCCAAUAAAAUGAAUGGCAUUUUACUUUUGAUCAAUAUAAAACUACUUUAGGGCAAAAAUAAAAAUGGGUAGUGAUGAAUGUAGAUGGGAAUGACAUUGCUGGCAUUUAUUAAAGGAGAGCAGUUUUUCUGUACGCAAUUUGACCAGACUCCAGUACUCUGAAGUAAACAGUAUUUCUUUAAUGUGACAGGCAUAUUUGUAAAUCUACUAAGGACUUAGUAAUAUAUCCUGAUAACGGGAAUAACAUCAUUCUUGAUCCAAUAAUUGCAAAGUGUGAAUGAUUCUCUAGAGCUUUGCAAAGGCCAAGAAUGUCUCUUUCAAAUGACAGUGAAUUUUCCAUUAUCUCUUAGUACAUAAUCGGUUUGGCGAAUUGUCUUCAGGACCCAGGAACUCUCUCUGUCCUUGACAUUGAGGAUGAUGAGUUGGGUGUUUGUGUAAAUGAAUGCAUGCCCUCCGACUGCAUUAACAGCCCAAAGAUCACGCAGAUUUGCGAAGCCAUUUCUUCACAGUUGGGAUGAAGCUUGAGACAGUGAAUAUGUGCGAGCCCUUUUACAUCUCUCCUGCGUCGGUGACUAAGGUUUUUAACAAUCACUUUUUUCAAGUGACUAUUGAUGACCUAAGACCUGAACCAAGUAAACUGUCAAUGCUGUGCCAUGCAGAUUCUUUGGGGAUUUUGCCAGUACAGUGGUGCCUUAAAAAUGGAGUCAGCCUCACUCCUCCCAAAGGUUACUCUGGCCAGGACUUCGACUGGGCAGAUUAUCACAAGCAGCAUGGGGCGCAGGAAGCCCCUCCCUUCUGCUUCCGAAAUACAUCAUUCAGUCGAGGUUUCACAAAGAACAUGAAACUUGAAGCUGUGAACCCCAGGAAUCCAGGAGAACUGUGUGUGGCCUCCGUUGUGAGUGUGAAGGGGCGGCUAAUGUGGCUUCACCUGGAAGGGCUGCAGACUCCUGUUCCAGAGGUCAUUGUUGAUGUGGAAUCCAUGGACAUCUUCCCAGUGGGCUGGUGUGAAGCCAAUUCUUAUCCUUUGACUGCACCACACAAAACAGUCUCACAAAAGAAGAGAAAGAUUGCAGUCGUGCAACCAGAGAAACAAUUGCCGCCCACAGUGCCUGUUAAGAAAAUACCUCAUGACCUUUGUUUAUUCCCUCACCUGGACACCACAGGAACCGUCAACGGGAAAUACUGCUGUCCUCAGCUCUUCAUCAACCACAGGUGUUUCUCAGGCCCUUACCUGAACAAAGGAAGGAUUGCAGAGCUACCUCAGUCGGUGGGACCGGGCAAAUGCGUGCUGGUUCUUAAAGAGGUUCUUAGCAUGAUAAUCAACGCAGCCUACAAGCCUGGAAGGGUAUUAAGAGAAUUACAGCUGGUAGAAGAUCCCCACUGGAAUUUCCAGGAAGAGACGCUGAAGGCCAAAUACAGAGGCAAAACAUACAGGGCUGUGGUCAAAAUCGUACGGACAUCUGACCAAGUCGCAAAUUUCUGCCGCCGAGUCUGUGCCAAGCUAGAGUGCUGUCCAAAUUUGUUUAGUCCUGUGCUGAUAUCUGAAAACUGCCCAGAGAACUGCUCCAUUCAUACCAAAACCAAAUACACCUAUUACUAUGGAAAGAGAAAGAAGAUCUCCAAGCCCCCCAUCGGGGAAAGCAACCCCGACAGCGGACACCCCAAACCCGCCAGGCGGAGGAAGCGACGGAAAUCCAUUUUCGUGCAGAAGAAACGGAGGUCUUCUGCCGUGGACUUCACCGCGGGCUCGGGGGAGGAAAGUGAAGAGGAGGACGCUGACGCCAUGGACGAUGACACCGCCAGUGAGGAGACCGGCUCCGAGCUCCGGGAUGACCAGACGGACACCUCGUCGGCGGAGGUGCCCUCGGCCCGGCCCCGGAGGGCCGUCACCCUGCGGAGCGGCUCAGAGCCCGUGCGCCGGCCACCCCCAGAGAGGACACGAAGGGGCCGCGGGGCGCCGGCUGCCUCCUCAGCAGAGGAAGGGGAGAAGUGCCCGCCGACCAAGCCCGAGGGGACAGAGGACACGAAACAGGAGGAGGAGGAGAGACUGGUUCUGGAGAGCAACCCGUUGGAGUGGACGGUCACCGACGUGGUGAGGUUCAUUAAGCUGACAGACUGUGCCCCCUUGGCCAAGAUAUUUCAGGAGCAGGAUAUUGACGGCCAAGCACUCCUGCUUCUGACCCUUCCGACGGUGCAGGAGUGCAUGGAGCUGAAGCUGGGGCCUGCCAUCAAGUUAUGCCACCAGAUCGAGAGAGUCAAAGUGGCUUUCUACGCCCAGUACGCCAACUGAGUCUGCCCUCGGGAGGUGGCCCAUUAUUGCUGGGAUGCGGUGUUGGUAAAGGUUUCCAGGACUGAAACUUUGAUUUUCCGGGAUAUGUUAAAUGGUACAGCCACUAAGUAUCACCAGAAAACCAGAAGCCCAGGAUCUUCUGCCUCCGCCAGCCUGUGAGCUGUUUCCAUGUUUUCAAAGCACAGCAGCAGUCGCUUCUGGGGAGUGCCAGUUAAAGUCAUGCAUCAGACCCUGCCAGACGUGGGCCUGCUUCUUGGCUCACCCACGUUUUGCCUUUCUCCUGCCCCAAAUCAGGCAGCUCCCUUGGAGCAGGGUUUCCUCAGAUGAGGACUGCAUUCUUUGAAAACAAAGAAUGUCGCCAAGGAAGAAACCUCACGCCAUGCUGUAGUGUUUCCUGUAAUCACACGAGCACAUUUAUAUAUGCAGUUUCCCAUGGAUAGGCGUGUGACCCUGGUUGAGUGGCACUUGCGGUUUCAUCUUGGUGGCAACUCCUUUGCAAUGCAGCUGGCAGCGACAUCCUUAUAAAAACAUGUGCUAAAGCUCUGUCCUCUGUUAGAGGUGCCUUUUAGGAAUACGGGGAGUGAAGGAAGGCCGGCAGGCAUCUCCAUGCAACUAGAUGGUUUGUUUGUUUGUUUGUUUGUUUGUUGUUCAUUUUGUUGUGUUUUUUGAGACAGGGUCUUGCUCUGUCGCCCAGGUUGUAAUGCAGUGGCGCAAUCUCAGCUCACUGCAACCUCUCUCUCCCGGGUUCAAGUGAUUCUCCUGCCUCAGCCUCCCAAGUAGCUGGGAUUACAGGCACCCACCACCAUGCCUGGCUAAUUUUUGUAUUUUUGGUAGAGACAGGGUUUCACCAUGUUGGUCAGGCUAGUCUUGAACUCCCAACCUCAAGUGAUCUGCCCGCCUCGGCCUCCCAACGUGCUGGGAUUACAGGUGUGAGCCACUACGCCCCGGCCCAACUGGAUGGUUUUUGAUUGAAGCCUAGAACAUCUGUAGAGACAAACUCUACCCAGUCUUUUCUAGACCCUCAACUAUCUCCAGUGUUGUUGUUUAAUCGUAGCCGGAUCAGGGAGUGAGUCUUUUAGGCAAAUGUUGGAUUAUAUAUCAAAGGAAAAGCUUAGUUUCAGAGAGGAGGAAGGGAAAGAGAUGUGAGGGAAGCAUUUCAUCAACCAGCUACGUCCCCCUUAGAAGGAUCACUGCAGCAGGUCACCGAGCAGGAGUCCCUCUGAGCGUCCCUUCUGUCUCGUUCUGCCCUAGCUGGCAGCAUAUGAACCAGGCAUGAUGCAGCAGGAGCAGUGAAUCUGGAGUCAGCCACUUGGCACCCUGGUUUCGCUGAGAACAAACUCUGAGAUCUUGGGUGACUUCUCAUCACUCUGGACCUCCAUUCCUGUGAAGUGACAGGUGUGGACCCUGAGGGUGCGGUGGUGAGCACACUGUCUCCUGCUGGCAUUCACCCCACUCAUGCUGGAAAGGAAGAUCCAGAUCGUACAAAAAUUAGAAAAAGAAAGAAUAAGAAGGGUCUGGUCCCAGUUCUGACUCGGCCAUUCUUACAGCUCUUUCUGGCUUUGAGUUUGCUUGUGGAAUUUCCUGGGCAGUUGUGUUAAAUCCGCCAGGUCACGUGCAGACAAAGCUGUGGCUGCGAGAGUUGGCUGGCCUCUUGGACCAGAAGCCAUCUCCAUAUCCUCAUGAGCGAUUCCAUAUCUCCACUCAGACCCUGUGGACUACAGUGUUCCGCUGUGGUGGCUGCCAAGAUGCCUUCUUAAACUUAUGCAAGGAAACCAAACCCUCCCACAGUUCCCAAGCAGACACUGGAAGCAGAGGCUUCUCACCCUUCCUGCUUUUUCACCACAAUCACCUUGAGCUCGUCCCUUGGACUAGAGUCUCCACAGUUCCAGUAAAAUUCUGCGGUGGGCUGAUGAGCUGCUUGCAUUUCUGUGACAUUUCCAGAUAUGAUUCUCAGUGGGAUUUUGGAAACUUUGAUUGCUCAAGCUCACCCUUCUUAACAUUCUGUAAUGGUUACAGAUGAGAAUGGAAAACACAUAUUUUAUGGAUGAGGCGUUUUGGUCUCCCCUGCAGUCGAUUUCUAGAAUCAAGUUUUAGAGUUCGGCUGAUGCAUCUGCCUGGGGACCUCAGAUGGGAGGAGUGUGUCAGUUGUACCCCGACAGAAAUGUCUCUGGGAUCUGUGGCUGGCUUGCCCCGGGCAUCUCUCCUUUAAGCUCAAGUUUUGAACUCUCUGCGGUUUUCCACCCCUGCCUUCUCAGCCACAUGCUUUUGGCCUUAAACGCUCAGUCUUGUGGAGUUCAACUCUGUCAAACGAUUGGAAAGGGCAUCCAUUUCCAGAUCUUUGGCAUUUUCCCCGCGCUGACUCUUUGAUGAUCCUUCACUGUGGCCUUUUCAAGCUCAGCUGUUCCUGUUGUAUUUGAGACGAGGGUGAGGGAAUGUGGUGGCCACAAAAGAACAGGGACUUGCAGCACAAAUGUCACUUCUGUCUCCCUUUUCAGUGGUAGCACGGAGGAGGAGGUGCUGCGUUGGAGGGAGGGGAUCCUCCAGGAGCUCUCUGGAGCCCAUCUAGGAAGCUAGAGUGUGUGGCCCGCCAGGAGCUCAGGAAGGAUACAGCCACUGUCGCAGGGGAAAGUGUUUGCUUCCCGUGGAGCCAAGCGCCCAAGACUCUCCGUAUCCUUCACCCUGACAGUUUAACUUCAGCGUUUCUCUGUGCAGUUGCGGUCACCAUGGGUGAGCACUGUCUGUGCACGUGCCAGGGAGGAGAUGGCUGGGACCACUGCACAGGAGGGCGCAGCCUGGCGUCGCCAUGAAAGUUGUCUCUGUGCCAUCUCUCCGGUCCUUGAGGAGAGCCCAGAAAGAUUUUAGGACCCAGGAGGUGCUUUUCCUCCAGCUGUUGCCAGUGUCCUUCUGAGCCUGGAUUCUCCGGGGAUUUCCGUCGUGGUGGAUGGACUUCACAUCAGCAGCAGUUCUGGUACAGAAUUGUAAUGUGUUUUCAUUUCUCUGUAGGAUUCACCUCUCACCAGCGUCUGUCUUAAAGGUAGGGCCAAUUUCAUGGAGCAUUUUUCUGUGUGUGUCCUUGUUGCUUUUGCCAGAAAAAGUGGAUUUGACAUGCGUGCCCCGAUGCCACCAUAGCCCCUAGGCCAACAAUGUCAUGGUCUAAACACCAAAAAGUGAUGCCCCGCAUUCCUUCCCUGGAUGGUACCGUUUCUUCUCCGUCUCUCUUUGAUGAUUCUUUGGGACCAAAGUCCUCUCCUUAGUGCGCCUACUUCCUGUGGGCAUCAUGCCACUUGGAACUUAUUGGAACUGGCCCGGGAGACUCUGCAGUCUGCGCCGUUUGAAAACCCUGAGAAAGAGAUGCCACCUCAACUUGAAUCAUGACAGCCCAUCGCUCAGUCUCACCCUAAACUCAUGGAGCUUGUUUCAGCUCCUCACUUCUUGACUGUAUUUGUACUAUGUUGAAAAAAUAUCCUGUCCACAAAGACAUAAGCCUAACAACCUAGAAAAACAACAGGGUACUACUGGCAUUACAGAACUUCUUUGCCUUUCAAAACAAAAGCAAAACACAGUGAACUUCACCACGGAGCUGCACAGCGUGGGGAACUCAUCCAUCACUUUCAAAAUUAGAGUCAUUUGAUCCAAGUUGGAGUCAGACACAGUAUUUGAGCUGCACGGCUUCUGGGUUCUCCCACCUUAUUUGAUCAUAUUCGAAAGAUUAUUUCCUGUGUUUGCUUUGAUUUGUUCCUCAGUACAUUAAAAUGAUCCACACCUUGAACACUGCCCUCUCUAGAAGGUUGAUUUUGAUCAGCCUUUUGAAGAUGGGUGUCGUUUCCCUAACUUAUCUCACAGAAUUUUGAGUGUUGUAUUUGGCAAGUUCUGAGAUUUGCCUUCUGUCUUAUGCCAAACACCCCUUUCUAAGAGCUGUCCCCGCUUAGUUUUAGAAGUACUAGGGGUUUUCAUACUUAUUUUAUAGAACACCCAUUUAUAUUUAUUUCUGUAUAUAGAACUAAAAAAAACAGUAGUGUUAAAAAUCUUUGUUGUGGUUUGAGCAUCUUUGCUGCUUUUGGAUUGAGAUGGCGAAUCAAGGCUUCACUUCCUCUCUCUUCUGUCUUUAGAAAGCUGUGAUCGUGCGUGCAAUUAUUUGAAAGGCAACAUAGUCAAUUAAGAAACCUGUAGUUGUUAAGGAAGAAAUUGUUGGCAAGAUAUCCAUACUGCCCAUAUCUCGUUGGUGCAAUAAUUAAAUAGCAAAGGAAAUCUGUAUUGGCAACUAUUAUAAUUCAAUAAUUCUUUUGUUUACUGCCCUUUUCUGUUCAAGAAUUUUCUGGAAAUUACUCCCUUUCACAUGGUUGAACUCUUAAGUUGACCAGUUCUCAUAGCUCUAUCACUAGAAUGGUUUGCAGAUACCCCAAACAUACUAUGAUAAAAUCAAAUUGUGCUACUUUUGACCCAUGUAAUUUACCUAAAAGUUGUAAUUGCUGACAGAGUACUGCCUUGAAUUUUGGUUUAAAACCUCUCUAGUUUCAAUGACAAGUAACAACUCAAAUAAUUCCAUAUUGUUUGAGGAAGAGGCCAUAAUCCUUCUGAAUUGUUGGCACUAAGUAAUGGGAUUUGGCCCAGUAAGUAUGACGGUCGUGUCGCCUAACCAACGCAGAGCAGUGCUUUUUGUGUGGCUGAAGCGAUGUGCUGACGAAAAAAGGAAAAUUCUAGGACAAUCGUUGGCUAAAAAUCACCUUAGGAUGAAAAAUUUGAGGCAAAUUUUUUUAAAUGACAGAAAAAGAUAAUCAUCUCACUUGCUUGAAACAGGAGCCAGCAUGAUCUCUGGAAGCAUCAACUAUCCCUCGUCGUGAUUGUUGAAAGCUCUUUCACUGUUUUGCAUUCUAGUUUGAAUAGUUUGUAUUGAAAUUGGAUUCCUAUCUUGUGUAUGUUUUUGGUGCGUAAAAGGGAAAAAUUGGUGUCAUUACUUUUGAAAUUUGCAGGACGAAGGGCAUGCUUUUGGUUUGCUGUAAGAUUGUAUUCUGUAUAUAUGUUUUCAUGUAAAUAAAUGAAAAUCUAUAUCAGAGUUAUAUUUUAAUUUUUAUUCUAAAUGAAAAAAACCCUUUUUACUUCAAAAAAAUUGUAAGCCACAUUGUUAAUAAAGUAAAAAUAAAUUCUA